GAUUUCAUCAGGGCUUUCCUGCUCCUUCUGGUUGCCUCAGUCCCAGGCAAGAUAGGGUCCCAGAAUCUUACAGCCCAGAGGCCACCUGUUGCAACUUCUUUUUUACAGAUGGAGUCAUCAGAACCCACUGUGAGGAAGUGACUUCUCCUUGAGGUCACCCAGACACUCCAAACAGAGCAGAGCAAAAGCGCCUAGAACUUGAAAUUUUGGACCUGUCUCCAACACCCUGGGGAUUUCCACCAGGAAGCCUUCAGUCACCAUCCAGGGGAUUUUUAUCGCCACAAAGGGUAAUUCCUGCUCCAUCCCUGCUGUGACUCAGCUGUGACGUUGAACCACACAAGCCAGAGAGAAGAAGAUAAAGUCAUCAGAGCUCCUACUCACCAGAGAGUGAGGCCCAGGCCAGGACUCCACAAGGCUGGUCCCCUGCCCUGGAGCAACUUAAACAGGCCCUCUGGCCAGCCUGGAACCCUGAGAUGGCCUCCAGCUCAGGCAGCAGUCCUCGCCCGGCCCCUGAUGAGAAUGAGUUUCCCUUUGGGUGCCCUCCCACCGUCUGCCAGGACCCAAAGGAGCCCAGGGCUCUCUGCUGUGCAGGCUGUCUCUCUGAGAACCCGAGGAAUGGCGAGGAUCAGAUCUGCCCCAAAUGCAGAGGGGAAGACCUCCAGUCUAUAAGCCCAGGAAGCCGUCUUCGAACUCAGGAGAAGGCUCACCCCGAGGUGGCUGAGGCUGGAAUUGGGUGCCCCUUUGCAGGUGUCGGCUGCUCCUUCAAGGGAAGCCCACAGUCUGUGCAAGAGCAUGAGGUCACCUCCCAGACCUCCCACCUAAACCUGCUGUUGGGGUUCAUGAAACAGUGGAAGGCCCGGCUGGGCUGUGGCCUGGAGUCUGGGCCCAUGGCCCUGGAGCAGAACCUGUCAGACCUGCAGCUGCAGGCAGCCGUGGAAGUGGCGGGGGACCUGGAGGUCGAUUGCUACCGGGCACCCUGCUCCGAGAGCCAGGAGGAGCUGGCCCUGCAGCACUUCAUGAAGGAGAAGCUUCUGGCUGAGCUGGAGGGGAAGCUGCGUGUGUUUGAGAACAUUGUUGCUGUCCUCAACAAGGAGGUGGAGGCCUCCCACCUGGCCCUGGCCACCUCUAUCCACCAGAGCCAGCUGGACCGUGAGCGCAUCCUGAGCUUGGAGCAGAGGGUGGUGGAGCUUCAGCAGACCCUGGCCCAGAAAGACCAGGCCCUGGGCAAGCUGGAGCAGAGCUUGCGCCUCAUGGAGGAGGCCUCCUUCGAUGGCACUUUCCUGUGGAAGAUCACCAAUGUCACCAGGCGGUGCCAUGAGUCGGCCUGUGGCAGGACCGUCAGCCUCUUCUCCCCAGCCUUCUACACUGCCAAGUAUGGCUACAAGUUGUGCCUGCGGCUGUACCUGAAUGGAGAUGGCACUGGAAAGAGAACCCAUCUGUCGCUCUUCAUCGUGAUCAUGAGAGGGGAGUAUGAUGCGCUGCUGCCGUGGCCCUUCCGGAACAAGGUCACCUUCAUGCUGCUGGACCAGAACAACCGUGAGCACGCCAUUGACGCCUUCCGGCCUGACCUAAGCUCAGCGUCCUUCCAGAGGCCCCAGAGUGAAACCAACGUGGCCAGUGGAUGCCCACUCUUCUUCCCCCUCAGCAAACUGCAGUCACCCAAGCACGCCUACGUGAAGGACGACACAAUGUUCCUCAAGUGCAUUGUGGAGACCAGCACUUAGGGUGGGCGGGGCUCCUGAGGGAGCUCCAACUCAGAAGGGAGCUAGCCAGAGGACUGUGAUGCCCUGCCCUUGGCACCCAAGACCUCAGGGCACAAAGAUGGGUGAAGGCUGGCAUGAUCCAAGCAAGACUGAGGGGUCGACUUCGGGCUGGCCAUCUGGUUAGGAUGGCAGGACGUGGGCUGGGCCCACAAAGGCAAAGGGUCCAGAAGGAGACAGGCAGAGCUGCUCCCCUCUGCACGGACCAUGCGACACUGGGAGGCCAGUGAGCCACUCCGGCCCCGAAUGUUGAGGUGGACUCUCACCAAAUGAGAAGAAAAUGGAACCAGGCUUGGAACCGUAGGACCCAAGCAGAGAAGCUCUCGGGCUAGGAAGAUCUCUGCAGGGCCGCCAGGGAGACCUGGACACAGGCCUGCUCUCUUUUUCUCCAGGGUCAGAAACAGGACCGGGUGGAAGGGAUGGGGUGCCAGUUUGAAUGCAGUCUGUCCAGGCUCGUCAUUGGAGGUGAACAAGCAAACCCAGACGGCUCCACUAGGACUUCAAAUUGGGGGUUGGAUUUGAAGACUUUUAAGUUUCCUUCCAGCCCAGAAAGUCUCUCAUUCUAGGCCUCCUGGCCCAGGUGAGUCCUAGAGCUACAGGGGUUCUGGAAACAUUCAGGAGCUUCCUGUCCUCCCAGCUCCUCACUCACCUUCAGUAACCCCCACUGGACUGACCUGGUCCACAGGGCACCUGCCACCCUGGGCCUGGCAGCUCAGCUUCCCCAACACGCAGGAGCACACCCAGCCCCCACAUCCUGUGCCUCCAUCAGCUAAACACCACGUCACUUCAUGCAGGUGAAACCCAGUCACUGUGAGCUCCCAGGUGCAGCCAGAGGCACCUCAAGAAGAAGAGGGGCAUAAACUUUCCUCUUCCUGCCUAGAGGCCCCACCUUUGGUGCUUUCCAGAAUCCCGUAACACCUGAUUAACUGAGGCAUCCACUUCUUUCAGCAGACUGAUCAGGACCUCCAAGCCACUGAGCAAUGUAUAACCCCAAAGAAAUAAUUUUUAGAAUCUCUUUCGAAGUUUUCCUAAAGUGUAUGGUUUGGGAGUUGUUUGUACUGAGCCAGGUUUGAAAAGGCCAUUGCUGAGUUUGAGGUGGUGCCACCAGUUUUGCAGGUGGCAUCAGAGGCUGGCAUGCUGGCAGGAACAUCCCCUCUUAGCCCCAGUCUUCUCUUUUCUAUAAUGAGACCCACCCCAGCUUGCCUCCCUCCCUGGCUUCUCUGACCCUCAAAGGAGAUGCCACGCAGGACAGACUGGAGAGAGAAGCCUGGGCAAUACUGCCCGCCUGUCAUGGCCUGGUGGUGGCCCACACCUAUCUUCUCACCUUGGAGGCCACACCCAACUUUCCAAAGACCCUGAGACAAGUCAGGACCCUACUACUCUCCCCUGCUGCUUUCCUGACAGCUUACUCUUCCUCCACCUGCUGAGCCUGUGCCAGACUCCAUUGCUCAAAUCGUUAGGGUUGCUUCUAUAAAAAUGGGUCAGUAGCCCUUCCUGUUCUCUCCAGCCCAGCAUACAGGAGGAUCAAAGGAGGUGACGGAGCAUCGUGGCACGGCAGUCUCAAUGGGUCAGAAACCCAGGCCAGCUGGGCUCUAAGCCUGGCAUCCUGUCAUGCUUAGUCCUUCAGCUGAAGAUCAGAGGAAGCCUCUCCCUUGCCCUCUCCAGCUCUAGGGGUUUUCAGGAGGCCCAACUGCAAUAAUGGAGCACUAGUGCUUUUAUGUGCAAUGGUGUCGUCCAUGCACGACAGCAGCAAACAUUCUGGGGCUGCUUUUUAUUGUUCCCACGGCUGACAGCGUGGCAGCGGAGACUGUGGAGGCAGUGGAGACUGACUUCUUCCUGCUGACAGCUGGAUGUCACACAUGAAGGUCUGGCCUAGCGAGUGAUGGGUCUAGGCCCUGAAACUGAUGUCCUAGCAAUAACCUCUUGAUCCCUACUCACCGAGUGUUGAGCCCAAGGGGGGAUUUGUAGAACAAGCCCCCAUGAGAAACAGCUGUUACUCUACACUUUUGAUUGCCUAUUUCUGAUGGCAAGAGAUACAUACUCUCUUCAAAGAGCAUGAGAUGCAGCCAUUCUUUCAGCAAAGCUUCAUUGACACCUGCACCUGUUAACUGUGUUCGACAUUGAAGGGAGAAAGGCAAGAUGUGCACUCUGGACUCAAGAAACUCUUAGUUCAGUGGAGGAAAUGAGCAGAUAAGUAGAUCAUUAUGAUUGAGAGUAGGAGAAGCUUAGAGAAAGCACAGAAUCCCAGAUCCAGCUGGUGAAGGAGGGAAGGCUUCAGGCCUUUAAGCUCAGCCUGAGAAUAUUGUGAAAUGCAGAGGAUGGGGAAAAGGGAAGAGUACCGACUUGAAAACGGAGAGCUGUCUUGGCUGAGGGCAGGGUCUGUGUGGCAGGAUGGGGGAGGGAGUCAGAAGGGUCAGAUGAACUGGAGUGUAGACAGCAUCAGAUGCAGCAGUGCCCACCGCCCCCCCCCCCACCCCCCGCCCUGCCCACAGAGCACCUGCUGGUAACCCUGGGCCUAUUGAAAGCAGGAUGAGAUGAUAAUUUAAGACACUGAAUGAUUUCUUUUCCAACAAAGCUCUAUGUUAAGUGCA